GUUGCUUUGCGGCGUUUUCCGCGGGGAAACUGUGUAAAGGGUGGGGAAACUUGAAAGUUGGAUGCUGCAGACCCGGCAUGGGUAGCAAGAAACUAAAACGAGUGGGUUUAUCACAAGAGCUGUGUGACCGUCUGAGUAGACAUCAGAUCCUUACCUGUCAGGACUUUUUAUGUCUUUCCCCACUGGAGCUUAUGAAGGUGACUGGUCUGAGUUAUCGAGGUGUCCAUGAACUUCUAUGUAUGGUCAGCAGGGCCUGUGCCCCAAAGAUGCAAACGGCUUAUGGGAUAAAAGCACAAAGGUCUGCUGAUUUCUCACCAGCAUUCUUAUCUACUACCCUUUCUGCUUUGGACGAAGCCCUGCAUGGUGGUGUGGCUUGUGGAUCCCUCACAGAGAUUACAGGUCCACCAGGUUGUGGAAAAACUCAGUUUUGUAUAAUGAUGAGCAUUUUGGCUACAUUACCCACCAACAUGGGAGGAUUAGAAGGAGCUGUGGUGUACAUUGACACAGAGUCUGCAUUUAGUGCUGAAAGACUGGUUGAAAUAGCAGAAUCCCGUUUUCCCAGAUAUUUUAACACUGAAGAAAAGUUACUUUUGACAAGUAGUAAAGUUCAUCUUUAUCGGGAACUCACCUGUGAUGAAGUUCUACAAAGGAUUGAAUCUUUGGAAGAAGAAAUUAUCUCAAAAGGAAUUAAACUUGUGAUUCUUGACUCUGUUGCUUCUGUGGUCAGAAAGGAGUUUGAUGCACAACUUCAAGGCAAUCUCAAAGAAAGAAACAAGUUCUUGGCAAGAGAGGCAUCCUCCUUGAAGUAUUUGGCUGAGGAGUUUUCAAUCCCAGUUAUCUUGACGAAUCAGAUUACAACCCAUCUGAGUGGAGCCCUGGCUUCUCAGGCAGACCUGGUGUCUCCAGCUGAUGAUUUGUCCCUGUCUGAAGGCACUUCUGGAUCCAGCUGUGUGAUAGCCGCACUAGGAAAUACCUGGAGUCACAGUGUGAAUACCCGGCUGAUCCUCCAGUACCUUGAUUCAGAGAGAAGACAGAUUCUUAUUGCCAAGUCCCCUCUGGCUCCCUUCACCUCAUUUGUCUACACCAUCAAGGAGGAAGGCCUGGUUCUUCAAGGAUCUAGAGAAUUCAAAUGAUCUGCUCGAGGCAAACAUAGGAUCGUCUGAGUUCCUUGCACCCUGUUCAAGGUUCAAGAGCCUAGGACUCUACUGCAGACCACACCACAACACUGUUGGAUCAUCAGACCUCUUCUAGCUACGAAUCCUUGACAAUUGAGAUAAGGUCCACUUACAUGAACCCUGAAAGUCAUUACAUAUGACUUAUUCAGCCCUCCCUUAUUCAAUUUGAUUCACUUGCCACCUUCCCAAGAUCUUACUCUUCAUGUGGAAAUGAGAGACUUAUUUAUUGCUCAGCUUGUUCCCUCAUUUCUCUAGGUAACAUGUACUACUAGUGGGAUCAUCAAACAAUAAGUAUUUGCAAAACUGGGCUUAGCGUGGUUCUAGGUGCUGUGCAAGUAUAUAAUGACACCCCCCAACCCAAAGAAAGUCACCUGGGGAGACCUGAAACAAUUAGAGAAACACACAAGGGGACCCUAAUUGAAUGUGAAUCUCUCUAGCCAACCAAAAGAAAGAGAGGGUGGGUUUAAGGGUAGUGAGGGACACUUUGUGAAGAAAUGACAGCUUGUGAGGACUCCAAGGUUGAGUAGAAUUUCAACAAAGAGCAAAGAAUGGAAUUGGAUGGUGUGUUCGAGAGAAGGAAACAGACAUUAUUGGAAUAAAGAUUCCAUGUAGGGAAGAAGGUUGAGUUGAAGAGUAGGGCCAGAUGAUGUGAAGUUUGGAAAGAGAGGCAGGGCAUGCUUUCUUCACCCACAACUAUAAUACAUCUUUGACCAUAAAAAGUGGUUGUUAUUGCUAUCAUUUGUUUUUGUUUUCACUUUGCCCCUUCAAGUUCUUGAAAAAGAUAGUCAUAAAAGAAGAGGGUAUGCCCUCAUUCAUGGAGCACAGAGAAGGAAGCCCUCUGUGAUGUUUCCAGAUGUGUAGGUUUAGGCUCUAGACCAGUGCUGGUGCCUUCCUGGGACUGCCCAAGCCAAUCACCAGGGAGAGGCUGCAGAUCCUUUCUCUGCUCAGCUCCGUUCGGGCUCCUCUUUUCUUGAAGAUUUGACAGAUAUUGGUUAAGUUCUUCAAAUCUGACAACUGGGUUCUUUGUGGCAAAGAAUAGGUGGCUAAGGAGAACUGGCUCUAACAGGCUAAUAGCCUACCUGGCCCCUUUCCAGCAGGAGAAAUGCCAUAGUCCUUCCCAGAAGCACAUCUUAUAUGCACAGUCCUCACAGAGUGUGUCUGUGCAUCAGAAUCAAUUAAUCAUGCCUGUCAGGAGGGGGAAUGGCCCCUCUGGCUGAAACAGUGGAAGGAGCCCUCGUGAUUGAAGACCACUUUGCCUUGGAAACUCAUGCAGGUCAGAGGGGAAAGUUGAGUCUAGAUGGCAUGCGGUAUUCCUUGGGUAUGUUUUCUCAUCCCUGAAAUUUGCCCAUGUCACCCAACUAACUGCUUGUAGCAAAGCUGUAUUGUCAGUGCAAUCCUUUGGGGCCUUGUUUGGGCCUGAAGAAGCCAUUCAUUUCUUAAAGAAGAAAAAGCUGGCAAAGUGGAAUUUGUAGUAACAGCUGUUAGUAUUUAAAACUUUUGUUUCAAGAUCUUCAGGCACUUAAAAAUGACUUUAAAUGGCCACUCUGCAAGAGUCUAUCUUUUACAAGGCAGCCUGUGAGAUCUUUCUCAAAACAAGCCUCAUCUCAUCUCCUCUUUUAUUGAGAUCCCCAUUGGUCCUCUAUUUUGUAUAGAAGUGGUUCCCAAACUUUUUUGAUUUAACACCCCAUCAGUAAACAAUUUUGAAUAGGUACUCUCAAUAUACAUAUAUUUCUUUUUAUAUUAUACACAUGUAUUACUUUCCUAAUAUAUUAUGUACAUUAUAAAACAUAUACAAAAGUAAUUUUUUUAAAGGCUGAGAUAAAGAUGAAGUAAGCAAUAGUUUAAAAUGUCUUGUCAAUUAUGAUGGCUUCAUACUGUCAUUAGCUAAUAUGUCAAAAGCACAAUAAAUAUGUCAGGGGAGUUCCAUUUAUAUCAUUUGAAUGAUAUAAAUCCUUAUAUCUAGUAGUUUUCAUGGAAAUUUCUAACUGUUUUGGCUUGACUUCUUGUUACAUGCAAAUAUUUGGUCAUUGUCUUCACUUUGUAAUAUGGCCGAAGAAAACUUGUUCUAAGGGCA